GCGAGAGUUGGGCGCAAGACGCCUUGUAGGGAGUGUAACUAUGGCCGGCCUGCGGAACGAAAGUGAACAGGAGCCGCUCUUAGGCGACACACCUGGAAGCAGAGAAUGGGACAUUUUAGAGACUGAAGAGCAUUAUAAGAGCCGAUGGAGAUCUAUUAGGAUUUUAUAUCUUACUAUGUUUCUCAGCAGUGUAGGGUUUUCUGUAGUGAUGAUGUCCAUAUGGCCAUAUCUCCAAAAGAUUGAUCCGACAGCUGAUACAAGUUUUUUGGGCUGGGUUAUUGCUUCAUAUAGUCUUGGCCAAAUGGUAGCUUCACCUAUAUUUGGUUUAUGGUCUAAUUAUAGACCAAGAAAAGAGCCUCUUAUUGUCUCCAUCUUGAUUUCCGUGGCAGCCAACUGCCUCUAUGCAUAUCUCCACAUCCCAGCUUCUCAUAAUAAAUACUACAUGCUGGUUGCUCGUGGAUUGUUGGGAAUUGGAGCAGUUUUUCAGACUUGUUUUACAUUCCUUGGAGAAAAAGGUGUGACAUGGGAUGUGAUUAAACUGCAGAUAAACAUGUAUACAACACCAGUUUUACUUAGCGCCUUCCUGGGAAUUUUAAAUAUUAUUCUGAUCCUUGCCAUACUAAGAGAACAUCGUGUGGAUGACUCAGGAAGACAGUGUAAAAGUAUUAAUUUUGAAGAAGCAAGUACAGAUGAAGCUCAGGUUCCCCAAGGAAAUAUUGACCAGGUUGCUGUUGUGGCCAUCAAUGUUCUGUUUUUUGUGACUCUAUUUAUCUUUGCCCUUUUUGAAACCAUCAUUACUCCAUUAACAAUGGAUAUGUAUGCCUGGACUCAAGAACAAGCUGUGUUAUAUAAUGGCAUAAUACUUGCUGCUCUUGGGGUUGAAGCCGUUGUUAUUUUCUUAGGAGUUAAGUUGCUUUCCAAAAAAUUUGCACAAUAAUUCAAUCCCUAAUACCACAUUUGGGGAAAUUAUUAUUGGUCUUUGGAAGUCUCCAAUGGAAGAUGACAAUGAAAGACCAACUGGUUGCUCGAUUGAACAAGCCUGGUGCCUCUACACCCCGGUGAUUCAUCUGGCCCAGUUCCUUACAUCAGCUGUGCUAAUAGGAUUAGGCUAUCCAGUCUGCAAUCUUAUGUCCUAUACUCUAUAUUCAAAAAUUCUAGGACCAAAACCUCAGGUAAGCCAGGUACCCUGACAUUGCAAUUAUAGAAAAUAUACUUGUAAGCACUCAACAUUUUUUGCUGCCAUUCUCUAUUUUUACACAGACUGAUUUGAGGGAUUUUUAUCAUAUUCAGCAUUUAAAAUUUUUAAAAAUCCCACAACUUCUAUAAAGUUCAUUCUUGGGUAGGUUAUGUGGGUUAUAGUUUUGGAUACAGAAGUUGUAGGAGUGGCAUUGUGGUAGAGUGUAAAGUGGCACAGUGGAGUCAGCCAAAUAUGGCUUCAAACCUCUUGAACAAGUUACUUAAACUUUCUGAGUUUCAGCUUCUACCUUUGUUAAACAGGCAUAACACCUGUCAUCGAAACUUGUGAACAUUACAAAUGAUGUAUUUAAAGCACCUACCUCAGUGACUGGCAUGUAGCAGGUACAAAAUAAAUGUUAGCUUUAAAAGGUAUUUUAAUCAAUUUUAUUAUUCCCAGGGCUUCAGCAGACAGUAAGUUUUUCCCUUUACACUCCUUUUAUUUUUUUUAAUCUGACUUAAUAUUAAAUGCUAUAUUUAUAGGAGGCAUUUUAUGUUUAAUUUAAAAGUAAAAGAUGCAGAAAUGAUUCUUGUAAGUUUGCUGUAGUUUGGUAAUACCAUUUCUUUGCUUUUAAAUAACUAAACCCCAAUAUCAAUCUGCUUGUCCUCCAUUUCACCCCCAACAGGGUGUAUACAUGGGCUGGUUAACAGCAUCUGGAAGUGGAGCCCGGAUUCUUGGGCCUAUGUUCAUCAGCCAAGUGUAUGCUCACUGGGGACCACGAUGGGCAUUCAGCCUGGUGUGUGGAAUAAUAGUGCUCACCAUCACCCUCCUGGGAGUGGUUUACAAAAGACUCAUUGCUCUUUCUGUAAGAUAUGGGAGGAUUCAGGAAUAAACUAGCUAAGACUGUGAUGGAAACUACUUGCUGUGUGGCACUUCCUGGUCUAAAGCUCUGCUAGACAAUUGCGGUGAGCCAGUCUCCAAGAAUCAGACUACAGAUAUUGCAGAUUUUGAAGAACAAGAACAUAUGUUGAAUAACAGAGAGAAUUCUACAUGUCAUUGUGAAUAGUAGGUUAUAUAAAAACAUACUAGAUGAUAAUUUCCUUACCUCAGAAAUGAAAUAUUAUUCUUAUAAUACCUUUUUGUGGUUGCAUGAACUAAUGAGUGAAUGGACAAUGAUGAAUAAAUGUGAAGCUGUAUUCUUAAUACCCACUGCAGAAGUGUCAUUAAAAUAAUAUACAGUGGAACCAGAAAGAGGGUUCUGUAAGAAUUAGCCAUAGCAGAACAAAAUUAUAGAAUUUUAAAUACCUCUACCCAAGUAGAGGUAUUUUUAUUCAGACACCUACUUUUUAUUUAUAAAAAAAUGCAUUUUCUAUUAUCAAGUUCACUUAUGAAAUAAAAAUUAUAACACAUAUUUUCCAUUUAGCGUGCCUAACAUCCUACCUUGCCUUCUAUGAGUCUUUCUUCUAAUACUACACCUCUGCCUUAUUUUAGUUCAGGGUUUCACUAAGUAACCCCUACAUUAAUAAAUGAGUAUGGAUAAUGCUAAUAUUUGAGCAAUACAGAGGAUUAAGAGAUCAAGAUACUUCACUGCCUAUUAGCCUAAUAGGGAUACCUACUUUCUUUCAAAUGCCAAAAAUUCACAUUAGAAACAUAAUCCAGAUAUGUGUUAUUUUAUAUAUAUAUAUACAAAACAGUAAAUGGUUUCUUAAAAUUAUUGCUAUUUUUCAACCCCCUUAAACUGGAGAAAAACAUUUAAUUAGUAAAACAUUAAUUAAUUUACUUUAAUUUUUCCCAUCUCUCAGUAGUGGCGGGGAGGAACACAACAGUUUUCAAUCUAUGUCUGCAUAGUUGUGUAGAGCUGCAGAAUUUUAGUUGGAUUUUUAAUUUGGAUGAUCCCUGACAGCCCCAAACUAGUCAGGCUAAUAAGUAUUUGAGGCAAAAUGGCUUUAAUCUAACAAUUUACUGAGUUUACCUGAAGUUGGCUAAAUAACACUGUAUGUUUAACUUCUACCUCUACAUAAGUUGAAUGCUGAUAAAAGGAACUAGUAGAUAACUAUGUAUAUUGAUAAGCACUGUUAAGAAAAUGCAAAAAUAUUUCUAAACACUUUUCCAAAUGUUUUCUACUUUAAGUUAGAAAUAGUUUCAAAUCUGAGAAUAAACACUAUAUAAUCUGCACUUUAUAGGUUGGGUGCAGUGUCUCAUGCCUGUAAUCCCAGCACUUUGGAAGGCCAAGGCAGGAGGAUUGCUUGAGGCCAGGAAUUCAAGACCAGCCUGGGAAACAAAGUGAGACCCUGUCUUUACAAAAAAUAAAAACAAAAAUUUAAAACUGUAUAAUCUGCACUUUAUGCUAAACUAGCUGUGCUCUUAAACUCAAUUUUUUCAGCUCUAAUAAAGGGCUUAAUUUGAUAGAAUUAUUCUACGAUUAAAUUUUGAAGACUGUUUUCACUCUCCUCUGCCGCCCAUAGCAAGACUGCUUCCAUAGAUUUCUCAGAACCGUAGCCAGUUCUGGCUAUUUGGUCAAGUCUGGGAUCCCUCUUACCUGCUAUUCUGCAGCUGCUUUCUCUGUCUUACAUUUUUUGGGCCACGUCUAAUCUUAAAGAGUAAACUCUACCCUUGGUUUGCAUAGUGUGCAUGACAAAAAUAACAAGAAUAAUGGUAAUGAUGAAAAUGAUAAGAGCAAAAUUUGUGGAGUGCUUUCCACAUUCCAGGUAAUGUGUAACAUACAAUUUAAUUCUUACAGCAGUCUUAUGGAGUGAAAAUACUAUUAUGAUUCCCGUUUUACAGAUGAAAGAAUGGAGGCACAGAAAAGUUACUUGUCUAAGUAACAGUCUAUCCUUAAAGUCCACAGUCUUAACCACUUGAUUUUUCAUAGUGAGGAAAAUAUCCCAGAAAGUUGCAGUUUCAAUUAAUCACUAAUUGUAGGGUAAUUUAACUAUACCAGUGAGUCCUACUAGCAGAAAUAUUUGGGCAACAUAAGCCCACUGACUGGAGCUUUUGUCUUAGCAUAAUAACCUGUUUCCAGCAAGAAUAUAACAGAAAAAAGUUUCCCAGCUUUCAAAGGUUUAUAAUAUUGAUUAAAAUUUAGAUAAACUUAACCUUACACAAAUGACUCUUACUUUCCUUUUUAUUGAGAGCAUUUUCUUUGGAGCAUUUUCUUCUUUGGAGGAUUAUACCUUGCUCAUCUUGGCACAAAAGAAGGCGAAAGGAAGUAACAUGGGAUUGGGAAAAGAGCAAGGAGAUAAAGUUUGAGGAAAAAAAAUCACCAUGUUGAUGUCUUCUUGAGUAGGCCAAGUUGCGUAUAAAGAGAAAAUGACAACAGGAGAUUUUAAGGUAUGAUAUAUUGUUAAGAGUAGUACAUAUUUAAGAAGAGAAAAUAUGUUUUUGAAAACAAAUUUAAACUUGAAAGGAUGAUUUUCAUAUUUUGAAGGGAUUUAUAACUUCACAAAGCAUCUCCAUUCUAUCUUGUUCAGCUUUACAUUUAAAAAUAAACUCUUCUUGUUCAUAUAAACCUUAUCUCUUACAUAAAGUGAAAUCUGUUAAUUUUUUGUUUUGACAAGGAUAAACUACUUACCUGCAUCUGUUUAAGAAUAGAUUAACUUAUUUUGAGAAGAAAUUCUGGGCACCAUUUUUGACCAUUGAAGACUUAUUUGUAAUUUAAUUUCUACUUUACAUUGUGAAUGUUCAUUUUCUAAUAAACAAGAUUAUUUUGCAUAUGUA